GCCAUGACGACCGCGGCUAGGUCGCGGCAGACUCGGUUGGUGACUCCGGGCGCGUCGAAGAUCUUGUACCUGUCGUUCGCAGUGGCUCACUUUCCCAGUAAUCCAUAAGAACAGCAGGGAUAACAGGGUCCCAUGUCGUUUUUUUGUCAGAAUUCCUCGACUGGCGACCCUGUGCCCGACAGGCUGCACCGCGCCCGGCGCACUGACUCCGGCCUCUGCGCGCGCCCCCUGGCCGGCUCCGGGGUGGGGAGGGGGCUUCGCAGAUCCCCAGAAAACCGCCCGGCGAGCCACGAGCCCGUGGACUGCAGGCUCCGCUUCCUCGCGGGGUGUUCACUUUGUAUCAGUGUGCUGAUUUGCCGCCAGUUAGAAGCACCUUAAAAAGGGGCCGGGGGCCGUAGGAGGGGGGCUUGUCUGAAGGAGGCUCUGGGCUUGCUGAUCCACGCAGCGGUUUGUCGCGAGGCUGCGGGGGAACGGCCCACGGCCGCGGUAACAGGGCUUCGUCUUCUUUGCAGAGCCAUGGGCAGCAGGAAGAAGGAAAUUGCCCUGCAGGUCAACAUCAGCACCCAAGAGCUUUGGGAGGAAAUGCUCAGUUCCAAAGGACUAACUGUUGUUGAUGUCUAUCAAGGCUGGUGUGGCCCCUGCAAACCUGUGGUGAGCCUCUUCCAGAAGAUGAGGAUCGAGGUCGGCCUGGACCUUCUGCACUUUGCAUUAGCAGAGGCAGAUCGUCUUGAUGUCCUCGAAAAGUACAGAGGGAAGUGCGAGCCAACCUUUCUGUUUUAUGCAGGAGGAGAACUGGUGGCUGUGGUUAGAGGAGCAAAUGCCCCACUGCUGCAGAAAACCAUCCUAGACCAGCUGGAGGCCGAAAAGAAAGUGCUGGCUGAAGGCAGAGAACGGAAAGUGAUUAAAGAUGAGGCUCUUUCUGAUGAAGAUGAAUGUGUUUCCCAUGGAAAGAAUAAUGGUGAAGAUGAGGACAUGGUUUCAUCAGAGAGGACCUGUACCUUGGCCAUCAUUAAACCAGAUGCAGUGGCCCAUGGAAAGACUGAUGAGAUUAUCAUGAAGAUUCAGGAAGCUGGGUUUGAAAUUCUAACAAAUGAAGAGAGAACCAUGACAGAGGCAGAAGUGCGACUUUUCUACCAACACAAAGCUGGAGAGGAGGCAUUUGAGAAGCUGGUACAUCACAUGUGCAGUGGACCAAGCCACCUCCUGAUCCUCACCAGGACUGAGGGCUUCGAGGACGUGGUCACUACCUGGCGAACCGUCAUGGGCCCCCGUGACCCCAAUGUGGCCAGGAGGGAGCAGCCAGAAAGUCUCCGAGCUCAGUACGGCACAGAAAUGCCCUUCAAUGCCGUCCAUGGAAGCCGGGACAGAGAAGAUGCUGACAGAGAACUGGCAUUGCUCUUCCCCAGUUUGAAAUUUUCAGACAAAGAUACAGAAGCCCCUCAGGUUGGACCCGCUCAUGCUUGGACUCUCUGACAGUCUUCUAACUCGUCUCUCUGCCUCCUGAUCAUCCUGCCUGCAGUCUAUCCUGGGUUCUGCAGUUGGACUGAUUUCUCCAUGGACUACAGGGUCAAGGUGAGAUUCUUCAGCCUGGUACAAGGCCCUCUGCCACUGACUCCCAGCUUCACCACUUCUUUCAGGACAUACCCAUGGCCCUGGCCAGACCAGGCCAGGCUCUUACUACUCUAAGCAGGUCUUAUCUUCCCCUUUCUAUUGUCUUCUACCCUCCUCUGUCCUCCCAGCACUUUUUGUUGCCUCUCAGCACAGCUGGCACUUCCAAUUUCAUAUCAUUCUGUUCUAUCUUCCAACUAGACUAACAUCUCCUUGAGGGUGGCUUUGUCUCCCCAGUACACAAGUGGUACGUGGUAUCUAGGUCUGUGGGCGGAAUCCAGUUUCCCUUCUUGCACUUUGUUUUGGGCGCUGCUGCUGAGUAAUCCCCUGGAGUCUUCCCCACUGAAGAGCCCACAGUGACCACUCAUAUACUGGCUCUCUCUAGACUCAGUGAAUCAGAAUUUCUAGGGAUGGGGCCCAGAAAUCUGCACUUUAAAAACUUCCCCAGGUGAUUCUAAUGCAGCCAACCCAGCCUUGAGACCCACUGCUCUCCUGUAUUUGCUACCUUGGCUAUAUAUUGGAAUCAUCUGGGGAGCUUUAAGAACCACUUAUGCCUGGAGCCCACCCCGAGAGAUUCUGAUUUAAUUGGCCUGGUGUAAAAAUUCCCAGGUGAUUCUAAUAUGCAGCCAAAGUAAAGAACCUCUGAUCUAUACAGGCCUCCUUACAGACUAGCUGCUUCACUGGUCACAUUGCACUUCUCAUUUCUCACAAAUGCACCUUCUUCUCCAUCAUGCUUAUCUGCCUGUAGUCCUCAUAUGUGCUUCCUCUGCUCAAAACGAAAGGCUCAUCCUCCCACCCACUCUCUCCUCUCACCUUCUUCAAGUGCAUCUCACCAUCCUCCUCAUCAGCUCUCUCCUGGCAGGGACUGUCACUUACUUCUCACUCUCCCUCCUUGAAUCUGGUAUAGAGUUGGCUCCAACGGGGCACUCAGUGUUGACUGACCAGCUGACUUGGGCUAGUUCCACUGAUUCUCAUACCAGGGCAACUCUAGAGGGUGCUUGGGCCAGAUGGUCCAAGAACAGAGCCUCUGCCCAGGAUCUCAGGGGCACCUGCUAGCUUCCCUGUGCAAGACACUCUUCCCAUAAUUUUUUUCAAAACAAAUCUCACCAAUCUCUUACCUUCCUCUUCAUUCCAUAUGAGGUUUGAUAUACAAAACAUGGCUGCAAGCUGCAGUUUAACAUGUGAAUGGCCCUAUUAA